GUCUGUCCUGGGAGCUGCAGUUACUGCAGUGUGUGUGUGAGUUUGUAGCAGGGUGGGAGAGGAGAGAAGGGAGGUGGAGGGGCUGCACCUGGAGUGAGGACUGUAUCUGUGUGUGCAAGCCGGGGCGACAGACGGCCUGGCACACUGAAGUCAGGUGCCGGGACCCAUGGGGCCUGCUGACUCAUGGGGACACCACUGGAUGGGAAUCCUGCUUUCAGGACAACGGCAGGACCCUGUGAGAAGAAAGCCAGAGGGAAGGGGCCAUGGCAGGCUUUCCACAGAGAGGCUUCCUGUCUCGGCCUCGCUUUGUACCGUAUGGAGUCCUCCAGCUGCAGCCCAGCUCACCCUCAAUGCCAACCCACUUGAUGCCACCCAAAGUGAGGAUGUUGUUCUGCCUGUGUUUGGGACCCCCAGGACACCCCAGAUUCAUGGCAGAUCCAGAGAGCUGGCCAAACCCUCCAUUGCAGUCAGCCCAGGCACUGCCAUAGAGCAGAAGGACAUGGUGACCUUCUACUGCACCACUAAGGACGUCAACAUUACCAUCCACUGGGUUUCCAACAACCUCUCCAUUGUGUUCCAUGAGCGCAUGCAGCUGUCCAAGGAUGGCAAGAUCCUCACCAUUCUCAUUGUCCAGCGGGAGGACUCAGGGACUUACCAAUGUGAAGCUCGAGAUGCCCUUCUGAGCCAGAGGAGCGACCCCAUCUUCCUGGAUGUGAAGUAUGGUCCUGAUCCUGUUGAAAUCAAAUUGGAGUCUGGUGUUGCCAGUGGGGAGGUGGUUGAGGUGAUGGAGGGCUCCAGCAUGACCUUCUUAGCGGAAACAAAGUCUCACCCACCCUGUGCCUAUACUUGGUUUCUCCUUGACUCCAUUCUGUCUCACACCACGAGAACAUUCACCAUCCAUGCUGUGUCCAGAGAACAUGAGGGCCUGUACAGGUGCUUGGUGUCCAACAGUGCCACCCACCUGUCCAGCCUGGGUACUCUGAAGGUCCGAGUACUUGAAACACUGACCAUGCCUCAAGUCGUGCCUUCAAGCCUGAACCUUGUGGAGAAUGCUAGGUCUGUGGACCUGACCUGCCAAACCGUCAAUCAGAGUGUGAAUGUCCAGUGGUUCCUAAGUGGCCAGCCCCUCCUGCCCAGUGAGCACCUGCAGCUGUCAGCUGACAACAGGACCCUAAUCAUCCAUGGCCUCCAGCGGAAUGACACCGGGCCCUAUGCCUGUGAGGUCUGGAACUGGGGCAGCCGGGCCCGGAGUGAGCCCCUUGAGCUGACCAUCAACUAUGGUCCUGACCAAGUGCACAUCACCAGGGAGUCGGCAUCUGAGAUGAUCAGCACCAUAGAGGCAGAGCUCAACUCCAGCCUGACCCUGCAGUGUUGGGCCGAGUCCAAGCCAGGUGCUGAGUAUCGCUGGACUCUUGAACACUCCACCGGGGAGCACCUGGGUGAGCAGCUGAUUAUCAGGGCUCUGACCUGGGAACACGACGGGAUCUACAACUGCACAGCCUCCAACUCUCUCACUGGCCUGGCCCGCUCCACUUCAGUCCUGGUCAAGGUGGUAGGUCCCCAGUCCUCCUCCCUGUCCUCAGGGGCCAUCGCUGGUAUUGUCAUCGGGAUCCUGGCUGUCAUUGCUGUGGCCUCAGAACUGGGCUAUUUUCUCUGCAUCAGAAAUGCCAGACGGCCCUCAAGGAAAACAACAGAGGACCCCAGUCAUGAGACCUCACAACCCAUCCCGAAGGAGGAGCACCCCACAGAGCCCAGUUCCGAAAGCCUGAGUCCUGAGUAUCGCAAUAUAUCCCAGCUUCAGGGACGGAUCAGAGUCGAACUGAUGCAACCACCAGACCUUCCAGAGGAGACCUAUGAGGGCUUGGAAUUGGAUUGCCAAUGAGGUGGUACUGGACCAGCACAUGCUGGGGUGAAAAGGAGGCUGGGAGUAGAGGUUGCAGAUCCAGCAGGAAAAAGGAGAGUUCUGGGCCAGGGCAAGGGCCUGGGUUCUAACCCUGCUUCCACCUCUGAUUCUCUGCAAGAACCUGAACAGAUUCCUUCCACUCUCUCGGUCCCUGAAGAGUGUAAGUUGGUACAUUCCUGGCAAUCUGUGUCUGUGGGCCCUGCCUAAUUUCUCUGCUUAC